AGCGGAGUGCGGCGGCGGCGACACUGAGUGGAAGGCAAAAUGGCGGCGGCGGCGGCGGUGGCCUGGUGUUAAGGGGAGAGCCAGGUCCUCACGACCCCUGGGACGGGCCGCGCUGGCCCGCGGCAGCCCCCCCGUUCGUCUCCCCGCUCUGCCCCACCAGGGAUACUUGGGGUUGCUGGGACGGACUCUGGCCGCCUCAGCGUCCGCCCUCAGGCCCGUGGCCGCUGUCCAGGAGCUCUGCUCUCCCCUCCAGAACUACAUCAUUCUGCCGGCCACAGUGGCUCACGCCUGUAAUCCCAGCACUUUGGGAGGCUGAGGUGGGUGGAUCACCUGAGGUCGGGAGUCCGAGACCAGCCUGACCAACAUGGAUAAAUCCUGUCUCUACUAAAAAUACAAAAUUAGCUGGGCACGGUGGUGCAUGCCUGUAAUCCCAGCUAUUCGGGAGGCUGAGGCAGGAGAAUCACUUGAACCCGGGAGGUAGAGGUUGCAGUGAGCCAAGAUCGUGCCAUUGCACUCCAGCCUGGGGAACAAGAGCGAAACUCCAUCUCAGAAAAAAAGAACUGCAUCAUUCUUUUUGACUUAGAUGUAUAUUAUAUAAAUGUACUAUGAAUUACUUGAACAAUCCUCCACUGAUGAACAUCUGGACUGGUGUCAACUUUUGCUGUUAUAAAUGAUGUUGCGAGGAACAGCCUACAUCUUCACAUACUUAGUUAAUUAUUUAUAUUGUAAAGAAUUUUAACAGUCCUGGGGACUUCCUUGAAGGAUCAUUUUCACUUUUGCUCAGAAGAAAGCUCUGGAUCUAUCAAAUAAAGAAGUCCUUCGUGUGGGCUACAUAUAUAGAUGUUUUCAUGAAGAGGAGUGAAAAGCCAGAAGGAUAUAGACAAAUGAGGCCUAAGACCUUUCCUGCCAGUAACUAUACUGUCAGUAGCCGGCAAAUGUUACAAGAAAUUCGGGAAUCCCUUAGGAAUUUAUCUAAACCAUCUGAUGCUGCUAAGGCUGAGCAUAACAUGAGUAAAAUGUCAACCGAAGAUCCUCGACAAGUCAGAAAUCCACCCAAAUUUGGGACGCAUCAUAAAGCCUUGCAGGAAAUUCGAAACUCUCUGCUUCCAUUUGCAAAUGAAACAAAUUCUUCUCGGAGUACUUCAGAAGUUAAUCCACAAAUGCUUCAAGACUUGCAAGCUGCUGGAUUUGAUGAGGAUAUGGUUAUACAAGCUCUUCAGAAAACUAACAACAGAAGUAUAGAAGCAGCAAUUGAAUUCAUUAGUAAAAUGAGUUACCAAGAUCCUCGACGAGAGCAGAUGGCUGCAGCAGCUGCCAGACCUAUUAAUGCCAGCAUGAAACCAGGGAAUGUGCAGCAAUCAGUUAACCGCAAACAGAGCUGGAAAGGUUCUAAAGAAUCCUUAGUUCCUCAGAGGCAUGGCCCGCCACUAGGAGAAAGUGUGGCCUAUCAUUCUGAGAGUCCCAACUCACAGACAGAUGUAGGAAGACCUUUGUCUGGAUCUGGUAUAUCAGCAUUUGUUCAAGCUCACCCUAGCAACGGACAGAGAGUGAACCCCCCACCACCACCUCAAGUAAGGAGUGUUACUCCUCCACCACCUCCAAGAGGCCAGACUCCCCCUCCAAGAGGUACAACUCCACCUCCCCCUUCAUGGGAACCAAACUCUCAAACAAAGCGCUAUUCUGGAAACAUGGAAUACGUAAUCUCCCGAAUCUCUCCUGUCCCACCUGGGGCAUGGCAAGAGGGCUAUCCUCCACCACCUCUCAACACUUCCCCCAUGAAUCCUCCUAAUCAAGGACAGAGAGGCAUUAGUUCUGUUCCUGUUGGCAGACAACCAAUCAUCAUGCAGAGUUCUAGCAAAUUUAACUUUCCAUCAGGGAGACCUGGAAUGCAGAAUGGUACUGGACAAACUGAUUUCAUGAUACACCAAAAUGUUGUCCCUGCUGGCACUGUGAAUCGGCAGCCACCACCUCCAUAUCCUCUGACAGCAGCUAAUGGACAAAGCCCUUCUGCUUUACAAACAGGGGGAUCUGCUGCUCCUUCGUCAUAUACAAAUGGAAGUAUUCCUCAGUCUAUGAUGGUGCCAAACAGAAAUAGUCAUAACAUGGAACUAUAUAACAUUAGUGUACCUGGACUGCAAACAAAUUGGCCUCAGUCAUCUUCUGCUCCAGCCCAGUCAUCCCCGAGCAGUGGGCAUGAAAUCCCUACAUGGCAACCUAACAUACCAGUGAGGUCAAAUUCUUUUAAUAACCCAUUAGGAAAUAGAGCAAGUCACUCUGCUAAUUCUCAGCCUUCUGCUACAACAGUCACUGCAAUUACACCAGCUCCUAUUCAACAGCCUGUGAAAAGUAUGCGUGUAUUAAAACCAGAGCUACAGACUGCUUUAGCACCUACACACCCUUCUUGGAUACCACAGCCAAUUCAAACUGUUCAACCCAGUCCUUUUCCUGAGGGAACCGCUUCAAAUGUGACUGUGAUGCCACCUGUUGCUGAAGCUCCAAACUAUCAAGGACCACCACCACCCUACCCAAAACAUCUGCUGCACCAAAACCCAUCUGUUCCUCCAUACGAGUCAAUCAGUAAGCCUAGCAAAGAGGAUCAGCCAAGCUUGCCCAAGGAAGAUGAGAGUGAAAAGAGUUAUGAAAAUGUUGAUAGUGGGGAUAAAGAAAAGAAACAGAUUACAACUUCACCUAUUACUGUUAGGAAAAACAAGAAAGAUGAAGAGCGAAGGGAAUCUCGUAUUCAAAGUUAUUCUCCUCAAGCAUUUAAAUUCUUUAUGGAGCAACAUGUAGAAAAUGUACUCAAAUCUCAUCAGCAGCGUCUACAUCGUAAAAAACAAUUAGAGAAUGAAAUGAUGCGGGUUGGAUUAUCUCAAGAUGCCCAGGAUCAAAUGAGAAAGAUGCUUUGCCAAAAAGAAUCUAAUUACAUCCGUCUUAAAAGGGCUAAAAUGGACAAGUCUAUGUUUGUGAAGAUAAAGACACUAGGAAUAGGAGCAUUUGGUGAAGUCUGUCUAGCAAGAAAAGUAGAUACUAAGGCUUUGUAUGCAACAAAAACUCUUCGAAAGAAAGAUGUUCUUCUUCGAAAUCAAGUCGCUCAUGUUAAGGCUGAGAGAGAUAUCCUGGCUGAAGCUGACAAUGAAUGGGUAGUUCGUCUAUAUUAUUCAUUCCAAGAUAAGGACAAUUUAUACUUUGUAAUGGACUACAUUCCUGGGGGUGAUAUGAUGAGCCUAUUAAUUAGAAUGGGCAUCUUUCCAGAAAGUCUGGCACGAUUCUACAUAGCAGAACUUACCUGUGCAGUUGAAAGUGUUCAUAAAAUGGGUUUUAUUCAUAGAGAUAUUAAACCUGAUAAUAUUUUGAUUGAUCGUGAUGGUCAUAUUAAAUUGACUGACUUUGGCCUCUGCACUGGCUUCAGAUGGACACACGAUUCUAAGUACUAUCAGAGUGGUGACCAUCCACGGCAAGAUAGCAUGGAUUUCAGUAAUGAAUGGGGGGAUCCCUCAAGCUGUCGAUGUGGAGACAGACUGAAGCCAUUAGAGCGGAGAGCUGCACGCCAGCACCAGCGAUGUCUAGCACAUUCUUUGGUUGGGACUCCCAAUUAUAUUGCACCUGAAGUGUUGCUACGAACAGGAUACACACAGUUGUGUGAUUGGUGGAGUGUUGGUGUUAUUCUUUUUGAAAUGUUGGUGGGACAACCUCCUUUCUUGGCACAAACACCAUUAGAAACACAAAUGAAGCCAGGUAUGGUGGCUCACACCUGUAAUCCCAGCGCUUUGGAAGGCCACAGCAGGAAGAACACUGGAACCCAGGAGUUUGAGAUCGGCUUGGGCAACAUAGUUAUCAACUGGCAAACAUCUCUUCACAUUCCACCACAAGCUAAACUCAGUCCUGAAGCUUCUGAUCUUAUUAUUAAACUUUGCCGAGGACCCGAAGAUCGCUUAGGCAAGAAUGGUGCUGAUGAAAUAAAAGCUCAUCCAUUUUUUAAAACAAUUGACUUCUCCAGUGACCUGAGACAGCAGUCUGCUUCAUACAUUCCUAAAAUCACACACCCAACAGAUACAUCAAAUUUUGAUCCUGUUGAUCCUGAUAAAUUAUGGAGUGAUGAUAACGAGGAAGAAAAUGUAAAUGACACUCUCAAUGGAUGGUAUAAAAAUGGAAAGCAUCCUGAACAUGCAUUCUAUGAAUUUACCUUCCGAAGGUUUUUUGAUGACAAUGGCUACCCAUAUAAUUAUCCGAAGCCUAUUGAAUAUGAAUACAUUAAUUCACAAGGCUCAGAGCAGCAGUCGGAUGAAGAUGAUCAAAACACAGGCUCAGAGAUUAAAAAUCGCGAUCUAGUAUAUGUUUAACACACUAGUAAAUAAAUGUAAUGAGGAUUUGUAAAAGGGCCUGAAAUGCGAGGUGUUUUGAGGUUCUGAGAGUAAAAUUAUGCAAAUAUGACAGAGCUAUAUAUGUGUGCUCUGUGUACAAUAUUUUAUUUUCCUAAAUUAUGGGAAAUCCUUUUAAAAUGUUAAUUUAUUCCAGCCGUUUAAAUCAGUAUUUAGAAAAAAAUUGUUAUAAGGAAAGUAAAUUAUGAACUGAAUAUUAUAGUCAGUUCUUGGUACUUAAAGUACUUAAAAUAAGUAGUGCUUUGUUUAAAAGGAGAAACCUGGUAUCUAUUUGUAUAUAUGCUAAAUAAUUUUAAAAUACAAGAGUUUUUGAAAUUUUUUUGAAAGACAGUUUUAGUUUUAUCUUGCUUUAACCAAAUAUGAAACAUACCCCCUAUUUUACAGAGCUCUUUUUUCCCCUCAUAACCUUGUUUUUGGUAGAAAAUAAGCUAGAGAAAUUAAGCCAUCGUGUUGGUGAGUGUUCCUAGGCUAAUGAUAAUCUGUAUAAUUCACAUCCUGAAACUAAGGAAUACAGGGUUGAAAAAAUAUUAAUAUGUUUGUCAGAAGGAAAAAUAAUGCAUUUAUCUUCCCCCCCACCCCCCGCCCCAUGGAAUAUUUAAUCUAUUUAAUCUUCUUGCAUUUAUUUCUCAAGAAUUACUGGCUUUAAAAGAAGCCAAAGCACUACUAGCUUUUUUUCCAUAUUGGUAUUUUUGAUGCUGCUUCCAAUUUUAAAAGGGAACAAAGCUGCCAUAAAUCGAAAUGUUCAAUACUAAAAGCUAAAAUAUUUCUCACCAUCCUAAGCAGAUAAUUAUUUUAAUUUUCAUAUACUUUUCCUGUAUAGUAACUAUUUUGAUUAUAUCAUCAAUGUUACCUGUUUCCUCUUUCAGAACAGUGCUGCAUAUACAGAUUGUUAUUGGCAAAGGAAAAUCUGGCUAUCUGGCAAUAUUUUACCUAAGCGCAGAUUAAUUGGUGAAAAAAUUAACUCUUAAGAUGGCCAUUAAUAAUUAGGAAAGUUUACAGAGUGGUCUUAGUAGAAAAUUCAAGUCCUCCUAAUUUAUUUAAGGUUCAAUAAUGCGUUCAACAUGCCUGUUAUGUAUAACGCUUAGGUUCUAAGGAAGAUUAAGGUUUCAUACCAAAAUACAUGUAGCUUAUCUUUUAGGAAGGGGAAAAAGGCUCCAUUUUGACCAUAGUAAAAUUUGUGUUGUGUUUUAUUUCCUUUUCUUAAGCUCCACUGAUAAGGGAUUGUUUUUAUCAAAAGUUACUAUUUGUAGAUUGGAGGCAUAAUUUUAGUGAUUUUCAUACUUUUAGCUUUCUUCGCAUAAAAGCUAAUUGAAACCGUAUAUGUAGUAAAAUUAAAGGCAGAGCUGUUGCAGUUGAAUUGGAGAGUUAGGGCAAAGAACACUUAUUAGCCCACACUUCCCACCUUUCUACAGGUGGUCCUUUCAGAGCUCAGCCUGAAAACCCACUACUGUGUUAUCGUGCGUCUUUUGGGGUUAGUGGUUCUUUUGAGAAUCUGAAGGAAGCUGUGGACUCUUCCUAGAAAAAAAAACCACACAUACACAUACAAUGUUGCAUGCAGUUUCAAGGGAUUUUGGACAUAUUGAAACCUAUCACAGGCUGUAGGUUAUGGACCUCUGUGCCAUGAGAAAAUUGAUACAUUAAACUAAGAACUUUGUUUUUAACUUACCAAUCACUACUCAGCACAUCUUAUAUAAGCUGAUAAUUUGUGAUGGAAAAGGUCUGUAGCAUGUGAUAUAAGGUGACCUUAUGAAUGCCUCUCUUGCUGGUACAUUAAGUUGUUUUAAUAUAUCAUUUGGAGGGGACUGAAAUGUUAGGCUCAUUACAAGCUUGAUACAGAAAUAUUUCUGAAGGAUUUCUAAUCAGAAUUGUAAAACAAUGUGCUAUCAUGAAAUCGCAGUCUUCACCUCAUGGUUCAUGGAACAUUUGGUUAGUCCCAUAAAAUCCUAUGCAAAACAAAGUAGUUCAAGAAUUUUUAGGUGGGUAGUCACAUUUAUAAGGUAUUCCUCUUACUCUUUGGGCUUUUUCAGUCUGAUUUAUUUAAAUUUUCAUUUAGUUGUUUUACUUUUGGACUAAGGUGCAAUACAGUAGAAGAUAACUUUGUUACAUUUAUGUUGUAGGAAAACUAAGGUGCUGUCUCCUCCCCCUUCCCUUCCCACAAAAUCUGUAUUCCCCCUAUUGCUGAAAUGUAACAGACACUACAAAUUUUGUAUUCUUUUUUUGUUUUUUGUUUUGAGACAGGGUCUCACUCUGUCACCCAGGCUGGAGGGCAGUGGCGCUUCACAGCUCACUGCAUCCUCAACCUUGGGGGCUCACGCAGUCCUCCCGCCUCAGCCUCCCAAGUAGCUGGGCAUGCGCCACCAAGCCCAGCUAAUUUUUGUAUCUUUAGUAGAGAUGGGGUUUCGCCAUGUUGCCCAGGUUGGUGUGGAAUUCCUGGGCUCCAGUUAUAUGCCCACCUCAGCCUCCCAAAGUGCUGGGAUUACAGACGUGACCCACCGCGCCUGGCGCAAAUAUGUAUUCUUUUAAAAUUUCCUCUGAUACUAUAAGCUUUUUGCAUUUAUCUGAAGCAGUAUACAUGCCUUUGGUAUCAGCAAUUUUAACAGUUUGGAUAUACUUAUCAGCUAUCUUAUUCCAAAACUACAUCUACUUCUUCCAGUAUAGAAUCUGGUGCUUCCUGACCAAAAAGAUGAGAAAAACAAUGUUAAAAAUAUAGAUGCUUUCCAUUGAAAUGGAGUGAAAACAUUGGUUCUAUAUGUUUUCUUUUAAAAUAAUUUUCUUAUUAAAAACUUGCUGUCUUUAUUAUACUUACCCUUUUUAUGCAUAUCAAUAGUAUUUAUAAGAUGUGUUCUAUAAUUAUGUAAUUGUAGAUACUGUUAUGCAUUGUCCAGUGACAUCAUAAGGCAGGCCCUACUGCUGUAUCUUUUCUACCUUCUUAUUUGUAAUAGAAACUAUAGAAUGUAUGACUAAAAAGUCACUUUGAGAUUGACUUUUUUAAAAAGUUAUUACCUUCUGCUGUUGCAAAGUGCAAAACUGUGAGUGGAAUUGUUUUAUUCUGACUUAAUGUGUUAGAAAUUAGAGAAUACAGUGGGAGGAUUUUUAGACAUUGCUGCUGCUGUUACCCAAGGUAUUUUAGAUAAAAAAUUUUUAAUAAACAUCCCUUUGGUAUUUAAAGUGGAACAUUUAGCCUGUUCAUUUUAAUCUAAAGCAAAAAGUAAUUUGGGUCAAAAUAUUGGUAUAUUUGUAAAGCGCCUUAAUAUAUCCCUUUGUGGAAGGCACUACACAGUUUACUUUUAUAUUGUAUUGUGUAUAUAAGUAUUUUGUAUUAAAAUUGAAUCAGUGGCAACAUUAAAGUUUUAUAAAAUCAUGCUUUGUUAGAAAAAGAAUUACAGCUUUGCAAUAUAACUAAUUGUUUCGCAUAAUUCUGAAUGUAAUAGAUAUGAAUAAUCAGCCUGUGUUUUUAAUGAACUUAUUUGUAUUUUCCCAAUCAUUUUCUCUAGUGUAAUGUUUGCUGGGAUAAUAAAAAAAAUUCAAAUCUUUCAA